AGUCUCUCGUCAUGGAAUACGCCUCUGACGCUUCACUGGACCCCGAAGCCCCGUGGCCUCCCGCGCCCCGCGCUCGCGCCUGCCGCGUACUGCCUUGGGCCCUGGUCGCGGGGCUGCUGCUGCUGCUGCUGCUCGCUGCCGCCUGCGCCGUCUUCCUCGCCUGCCCCUGGGCCGUGUCCGGGGCUCGCGCCUCGCCCGGCUCCGCGGCCAGCCCGAGACUCCGCGAGGGUCCCGAGCUUUCGCCCGACGAUCCCGCCGGCCUCUUGGACCUGCGGCAGGGCAUGUUUGCGCAGCUGGUGGCCCAAAAUGUUCUGCUGAUCGAUGGGCCCCUGAGCUGGUACAGUGACCCAGGCCUGGCAGGCGUGUCCCUGACGGGGGGCCUGAGCUACAAAGAGGACACGAAGGAGCUGGUGGUGGCCAAGGCUGGAGUCUACUAUGUCUUCUUUCAACUAGAGCUGCGGCGCGUGGUGGCCGGCGAGGGCUCAGGCUCCGUUUCACUUGCGCUGCACCUGCAGCCACUGCGCUCUGCUGCUGGGGCCGCCGCCCUGGCUUUGACCGUGGACCUGCCACCCGCCUCCUCCGAGGCUCGGAACUCGGCCUUCGGUUUCCAGGGCCGCUUGCUGCACCUGAGUGCCGGCCAGCGCCUGGGCGUCCAUCUUCACACUGAGGCCAGGGCACGCCAUGCCUGGCAGCUUACCCAGGGCGCCACAGUCUUGGGACUCUUCCGGGUGACCCCCGAAAUCCCAGCCGGACUCCCUUCACCGAGGUCGGAAUAACGUCCAGCCUGGGUGCAGCCCACCUGGACAGAGUCCGAAUCCUACUCCAUCCUUCAUGGAGACCCCUGGUGCUGGGUCCCUGCUGCUUUCUCUACCUCAAGGGGCUUGGCAGGGGUCCCUGCUGCUGACCUCCCCUUGAGGACCCUCCUCACCCACUCCUUCCCCAAGUUGGACCUUGAUAUUUAUUCUGAGCCUGAGCUCAGAUAAUAUAUUAUAUAUAUUAUAUAUAUAUAUAUAUUUCUAUUUAAAGAGGAUCCUGAGUUUGUGAAUGGACUUUUUUAGAGGAGUUGUUUUGGGGGGGGGGGGGUCUUCGACAUUGCCGAGGCUGGUCUUGAACUCCUGGACUUAGACGAUCCUCCUGCCUCAGCCUCCCAAGCAACUGGGAUUCAUCCUUUCUAUUAAUUCAUUGUACUUAUUUGCUUAUUUGUGUGUAUUGAGCAUCUGUAAUGUGCCAGCAUUGUGCCCAGGCUAGGGGGCUAUAGAAACAUCUAGAAAUAGACUGAAAGAAAAUCUGAGUUAUGGUAAUACGUGAGGAAUUUAAAGACUCAUCCCCAGCCUCCACCUCCUGUGUGAUACUUGGGGGCUAGCUUUUUUCUUUCUUUCUUUUUUUUGAGAUGGUCUUGUUCUGUCAACCAGGCUAGAAUGCAGCGGUGCAAUCAUGAGUCAAUGCAGCCUCCAGCCUCGACCUCCCGAGGCUCAGGUGAUCCUCCCAUCUCAGCCUCUCGAGUAGCUGGGACCACAGUUGUGUGCCACCACACUUGGCUAACUUUUUAAUUUUUUUGCGGAGACGGUAUUGCUAUGUUGCCAAGGUUGUUUACAUGCCAGUACAAUUUAUAAUAAACACUCAUUUUUCCUCCC